AGUCUGCGGGCCUCCGGGGCAGCGGCGAGGCCGGAGCGUCGCGGCGGAGAGGACGAGACCGGGACAAGACCAGGGCAGGAGGGAGCCGGCCAGCCGCGAGAACCCCGCACGCCCGGCAAGAUGCUGUCCUGGCGGCUGCAGACGGGCCCCGAGAAGGCCGAGCUCCAGGAGCUCAACGCCCGGCUCUAUGACUACGUGUGUCGGGUGCGGGAGCUGGAGCGCGAAAACCUACUCCUGGAGGAGGAGCUGCGCGGCCGGCGCGGGCGAGAGGGCCUGUGGGCCGAGGGGCAGGCCCGCUGCGCCGAGGAGGCGCGCAGCUUGCGGCAGCAGCUGGACGAGCUGAGCUGGGCCACUGCGCUGGCGGAGGGCGAGCGGGACGCUCUGCGGCGCGAGCUGCGGGAGCUGCAGCGCCUGGAUGCGGAGGAGCGCGCCGCCCGCGGCCGCCUGGACGCCGAGCUGGGUGCGCAGCAGCGCGAGCUGCAGGAGGCGCUGGGCGCGCGCGCCGCCCUCGAGGCGCUGCUGGGCCGGCUGCAGGCCGAGCGCCGAGGCCUCGACGCGGCCCACGAACGCGACGUGAGGGAGCUGCGCGCGCGCGCCGCCAGCCUUACCAUGCAUUUCCGCGCCCGCGCCACCGGCCCCGCCGCGCCGCCGCCACGCCUGCGGGAGGUGCACGACAGCUACGCACUGCUGGUGGCCGAGUCGUGGCGGGAGACGGUGCAGCUGUACGAGGACGAGGUGCGCGAGCUGGAGGAGGCGCUGCGGCGCGGCCAGGAGAGCAGACUCCAGGCGGAGGAAGAGACGCGGCUGUGCGCGCAGGAGGCAGAGGCGCUGCGGCGCGAGGCGCUCGGGUUGGAGCAGCUGCGCGCGCGGCUGGAGGACGCGCUGCUGCGGAUGCGCGAGGAGUACGGGAUACAGGCCGAGGAGCGGCAGAGAGUGAUUGACUGCCUGGAGGAUGAGAAGGCAACCCUCACCUUGGCCAUGGCUGACUGGCUGCGGGACUAUCAGGACCUCCUGCAGGUGAAGACCGGCCUCAGUCUGGAGGUGGCGACCUACCGGGCCUUAUUGGAAGGAGAAAGUAAUCCAGAGAUAGUGAUCUGGGCUGAGCACGUUGAAAACAUGCCGUCAGAAUUCAGAAACAAAUCCUAUCACUAUACCGACUCACUACUACAGAGGGAAAAUGAAAGGAAUCUAUUUUCAAGGCAGAAAGCACCUUUGGCAAGUUUCAAUCACAGCUCGGCACUGUAUUCUAACCUGUCAGGGCACCGUGGAUCUCAGACGGGCACAUCUAUUGGAGGUGAUGCCAGAAGAGGCUUCUUGGGCUCGGGAUAUUCUUCCUCGGCCACUACCCAGCAGGAAAACUCAUACGGAAAAGCCGUCAGCAGUCAAACCAACGUCAGAACUUUCUCUCCAACCUAUGGCCUUUUAAGAAAUACUGAGGCUCAAGUGAAAACAUUCCCUGACAGACCAAAAGCCGGAGAUACAAGGGAGGUCCCCGUUUACAUAGGUGAAGAUUCCACAAUUGCCCGCGAGUCGUACCGGGAUCGCCGAGACAAGGUGGCAGCAGGUGCUUCGGAAAGCACACGGUCAAAUGAGAGGACCGUCAUUCUGGGAAAGAAAACAGAAGUGAAAGCCACGAGGGAGCAAGAAAGAAACAGACCAGAAACCAUCCGAACAAAGCCAGAAGAGAAAAUGUUCGAUUCUAAAGAGAAGGCUUCCGAGGAGAGAAACCUAAGAUGGGAAGAAUUGACAAAGUUAGAUAAGGAAGCGAGACAGAGAGAAAGCCAGCAGAUGAAGGAGAAGGCUAAGGAGAAGGACUCACCGAAGGAGAAGAGCGUGCGAGAGAGAGAGGUGCCGAUUAGUCUAGAAGUAUCCCAGGACAGAAGAGCAGAGGUGUCCCCGAAAGGUUUGCAGACGCCUGUGAAGGAUGCUGGUGGUGGGACCGGUAGAGAGGCAGAAGCAAGAGAGCUACGGUUCAGGUUGGGCACCAGUGAUGCCACUGGUUCUCUGCAAGGCGAUUCCAUGACAGAAACCGUAGCAGAAAACAUCGUUACCAGUAUCCUGAAGCAGUUCACUCAGUCUCCAGAGACAGAAGCAUCUGCUGAUUCUUUUCCAGACACAAAAGUCACUUACGUGGACAGGAAAGAGCUUCCUGGGGAAAGGAAAACAAAGACUGAAAUAGUUGUGGAGUCUAAACUGACUGAGGAUGUUGAUGUUUCCGAUGAAGCUGGCCUGGACUACCUUUUAAGCAAGGAUAUUAAGGAAGUGGGGCUGAAAGGCAAGUCAGCCGAGCAGAUGAUAGGAGACAUCAUCAACCUCGGCCUGAAAGGGAGGGAGGGGAGAGCAAAGGUCGUCAACGUGGAGAUCGUGGAGGAGCCCGUGAGUUAUGUCAGCGGGGAGAAGCCGGAGGAGUUUUCCGUCCCAUUCAAAGUGGAGGAGGUCGAAGAUGUGUCGCCAGGCCCCUGGGGGUUGGUUAAGGAGGAGGAAGGUUAUGGAGAAAGCGAUGUCACAUUCUCAGUUAAUCAGCAUCGAAGGACCAAGCAGCCUCAGGAGAACACGACUCACGUGGAAGAAGUGACAGAGGCAGGUGAUUCAGAGGGCGAGCAGAGUUAUUUUGUGUCCACUCCAGAUGAACACCCCGGGGGGCACGACAGAGAUGACGGCUCGGUGUACGGGCAGAUCCACAUCGAGGAGGAAUCCACCAUCAGGUACUCUUGGCAGGAUGAAAUCGUGCAGGGGACUCGAAGGAGGACACAGAAGGACGGUGCAGUGGGCGAGAAGGUUGUGAAGCCCUUGGAUGUCCCAGCGCCCUCUCUGGAGGGGGACCUGGGUUCCACUCACUGGAAAGAACAAGCUAGAAGCGGUGAAUUUCAUGCCGAACCCACAGUCAUUGAAAAAGAAAUUAAAAUACCCCACGAAUUCCACACCUCCAUGAAGGGCAUCUCCUCCAAGGAGCCCCGGCAGCAGCUGGUGGAGGUCAUCGGGCAGCUGGAGGAAACCCUUCCCGAGCGCAUGAGGGAGGAGCUGUCCGCCCUCACCAGAGAGGGGCAGGGUGGGCCGGGGAGCGUUUCCGUGGAUGUCAAGAAGGUCCAGGGUGCUGGUGGCAGUUCCGUGACCCUGGUUGCUGAAGUCAACGUCUCACAAACUGUGGAUGCCGAUCGGUUAGACCUGGAGGAGCUGAGCAAAGAUGAGGCCAGUGAGAUGGAGAAGGCUGUGGAGUCGGUGGUUCGGGAGAGCCUGAGCAGGCAACGCAGCCCAGCGCCUGGCAGCCCAGAUGAGGAAGGUGGAGCGGAGGCCCCGGCUGCUGGCAUUCGCUUUAGGCGUUGGGCCACCCGGGAGCUGUACAUCCCUUCAGGCGAGAGCGAGGUUGCUGGUGGGGCCUCUCACAGCUCGGGACAGCGCACUCCCCAGGGCCCAGUGUCGGCCACUGUGGAGGUCAGCAGCCCCACAGGCUUUGCCCAGUCACAGGUGCUGGAGGAUGUGAGCCAGGCUGCAAGGCACAUAAAACUCGGCCCCUCUGAAGUCUGGAGGACUGAGCGAAUGUCAUAUGAAGGACCCACUGCAGAAGUGGUGGAGUUCUGGAAGCUGGGAAGUCUCAAGGUGCCAACAGUUUCAUUUCCUGGUGAGGGCUCUCUUCCGGGCCUGCAGACGGCUGUCUUCUCACUGUGUCCUCACAUGGUGGAGAGAGAGAUCAUCUCUCUGGUGUCUCUCCUUAUAAAGCACUAAUCCCAUUCAUCAGGGCUCCACCCUCAUAACCUAAUCACCUCUCCAAGACCCCACCCCCAAUACCAUCCCUUUGGGGAUUAGGGCUUCAACGUGAAUUGGGAGCAUAUGAACAUUCACCCCUUAGCUGACUCCACCCAUGUCAACUAGAUAGGACACACGGUGAGUAGUGACAUCUUACACGUUUUUAGCACACUGCUGAUGUCCGACAGGCCUGGGUCUGGGACCAGUGUGUACCAGCAAGCAUGGUCUGUGGGGUCAGCUGUCACGCUCCUGAGGAAGACAAUGGUCCCUGCUUCUCUCCACCCUGUCGUGGCUCUACUGAGUUUAUUUUCCCCAUCAAUACUGGAGGUGGUGCCCUGCACAAAUGGCCCCAGGGUGGUUUUGAUGUCCCACUGGGGGCUGGAGGGGAGGGCCCUGUGCUGCAAUCUGCUGUCAUAGCACCAGCCUGCAGCCUCAUGGCCACAGUCUGUGGGACCAGGGGAGGGAGGGGAAGGGACAUCACUGCCCACACCUGCACCCCUACCCCUGGGUGUUCCAUCCACCUCGAUCUGGCACUGGAUCUCCUCGUUGACAUCGUGGAGGAAGGCACUCAAAGCUUCCUGUUCGACUUUGCCAUCCUCACACGACUAUGGCCUCCUUCCAGGGGGCUGAAGACUGCUGUGUACACGAUAGUGUGCCAACUCAGGAAGCAGCUCCAGGUGGCAUCCAGGUUUGUCCUGCCUGCAGUGGAGGCCACAGGAGGGAUGCGAAGCAGCAGGGAGUCUGCGGUCUUCCCCCCGCAGCCUCCGGCUAGCCUUUCUUUUCACUCCCUUACACCUGCCUCCUGGGCCCCAGGCCAAGUCAGGUGUGUCGGCCUCCUGCCCCUCCUACUGGGCUCUUUCUCAAACCCCUUUUCAGGCUCCGAAGAACUCUGAGGCAGGCUGCACUUUGAAAACACAUGCUGACAGCAGCGUGUUCAGGUUUCCCUUUAUUAGCGUUUUCUUCUCAUGUUAUUCUCAAUCCCUAUUAGCCUCCUAUAAGAAAGGACUUCCUGAAGUUCACUGUCCAGAUCUAACUCCACACCUAUGCAAGGAGCUGUGUGUACAAGCAGAUGCCGGGCUGACUCCUGCACAGGGCGCACUGAACUGUUGAAGAGAAGUUUUUCAGCCACAGUAGUGCUGAUGGGUAAAAAUUCUUGUUGGCAAGAAAAACCACUUAGGUGAUAGAAAACUGCUUUAUAGCAUAUAUCACCCUGAAGGGCAUCCACUGUCAAAAUGUGGCCCACGGGAGGCUUAUGGUCUCACUGUUGCAUGUUGGGGCCAACAGUUGGCCUUGGAAAUCUGUAUCCUGACUGUUGAAUUCCAUUUUCUAGGCGGAGGUGAUUUGUACAGCACCCUAAAUGACAGUGCCCAGGAAUGUCCUAGGCUUUUUCAGGGUGGGGGCCUCAGUCUGCUGUUGUGCCGGGCCGGGCCUUCCCCAGCAGGGUGUCCUGAGGGAUGCUGGUGCAGAAGGCCACUUUGGCUUUUGAUGCCUGCCUUGGCUUCGAAGCAACCUUGGGGGCCCUGCAGACAAGCAGAGGGUGGGGUGAGUGUGGUGCCCCUCAGCCCCCCACACCGUUCCCAUCCAGCCUUUGCUGCCCAGCAGGUGCCCAGACCCAUUUAUGAGAAGACUUGGUAGGGGCUAUAAAUGAGAGGAGAAUUGUAGCACAGAGCAUAAAACAUGAGAUGUUUUCCUCCCAUCUUUUAUUUUUUUAAUUUUUUUUUUUUCAGACAGAGUCUCACUCUGUCACCCAGGCUGGAGUGCAGUGGCCCCAUCUCGGCUCCCUGCAACUUCCGCCUCCCAGGUUCAAGCAACUCUCAUGCCUCAGUCUCCCGAGUAGCCAGGAUUACAGGCACAUGCCACCACGCCCAGCUAAUUUUUGUAUUUUUAGUAGAGACGAAGUUUUGCCAUGUUGGCCAGUCUGGUCUCAAACUCCUGGCCUCAAGUGAUCCACCGCCUCGGCCUCCCAAGGUGCUGGGAUUAUAGGCAUGAGUCACCUCGCCUGGCCCCUCCCAUCUUUUAAAAUCACCUGUGACCAUCCUCACUGAGCUGAGGCCCUCAACCCUUAGCUGGCUUGGUGAGCAGGACAUGGGUGAGGAGGAUGGUCAGGGUUGCACUGGAGGCCUCCCUGGCUCGCCUUCCCUGCCCUCAAAGGGGAUGGCGCCCUGCUGGCCAGGUUGUGUCUGCUCCGGGCUGUGGCCCUGUUUCCCUGAGCAGACUCAGGCAGCCCUGGGGCUGCUCUCUGCGGACCAGGCUCUGUGAGGUAGGCCCUCCACGGCAGAGCGCUGGGCCUCUGCUCGGGCUGAGAAAGGACGUAGGGGCCAGCCUUUAAGGUCAGUCAGUGAACCUUCCGGCUCCAGUCCUGACGGGCAUCCGAGGGCAGAGGGAAGCCGGAAGCAGGGCUGCAGGAGGCCACAGGGAUUCCCGGGGCCCUCCCCCUGCAGCAGGUGCCUUAGCCUGCAGGGGCUGGUCUGCAGGAAGACAACAUCCAGCAUAUAUUUCUGACUUAAAGGAUGAAUUAUUUUUAAAUACCUGGGCAAGGAAGAUCUUUUACAACUCGGGUUUCAAAGGAACUUGUCCUUUAUGCAAGUUAUGGGAAGUCAGCAAAACAUUCCAGAGAAGGUUACACAGAACCUUCUAGAACCAGCUUUCUCUUGAGAUUCUGAAUGGAAAGGGAAUGAGAUAGAGAAAGUGUGAGGGACGCCAACUCACGUGGACAGCAUGCCCAUGGCCUGCUGGGUGGCCAGAGUCCUUUUGUCCUGCGGUCCAUAUAAGAGGGUCUGGAUCUGGAGACACUGUAGAACACCAAGCAGCUAUCAUGAGGCUAUGGAAGUGUCGCUGAGAGCAGGAAACUAAGGUCUCCCUUGAAUGAGAGAAAGAUGACCUCAUUCUUAGGCCCUGCUGUGAUGGAAUUAGCAUGCUCCUGGGAUGUCUCCUAGUGACUGACCUUUGGUUUGGAUGUUCUGAGGGAUCUAGGCAAAAGUGAACAGUUUUAGCACUAUUUCACAAAACUCUCUGUGACUAUCUGUAUGCAAAAAAUAGAUUUAAAAGUAGUAUUUUUAAAAAUAAAGGCAAGAACCUUGGUACUGACCAGAGGAUGGGCUCCAGUUUCUAUUUUUAAAUGUGGCCCUUGUUAUAGCCUGGAAAAGAUUUAAAAAAAUAGUUUUGUUUUUUUUGUAAACACAUACUCUACUUUUAUUAAUAUAUAGGCUGUCUAUACUCUUGACUACACAGCAAUGUCUUAGUUAUUAGGAACCAAAUAUUCAGCUUAUGGACUACCCAGGGCUGGCUUUGGCUUGAUUUCUCCCUUCUGCUUACUUUAAGUCUUGCCAUUUGAUUGCUUGUAGUAGGCUAGGGCAAAUCAAGGAGAGGAGAAAGAUUAAAGUUGUGCCCAAAAUGGCCAAAAUAAUUUUGAGAAAGAAUGAGGUGGAGAGGUGGAGGAACUUGCUUUACUGAAUGCCAAAGACCCUUUUAUUUUUUUAAAUAAAGUAAUUAAGACAGCAUGUUUGUCACCCGGGGUAGACAAAAAGACCAGUGGAACAGGGCAGAGAGCCCAAGCCUUGACAGAUGACAGAAAUGGCCUUGCGGGAUUGGUGAGGAAGAGGUGGGCUAGUCAAUAAAUGGGUACUGGGACCGCUGGUUUUCCAAAUGGAAGAAAAUGGAUCACUACCCCAAAUCAAACACAAAUAUUAAGCUCAAGAAAGAUUUGAAGGACUAAGUGUGAAAUGCAAAACUUGGAGCUUUUAGAUGAAAAUACUGGAAAAUAUAUAUAUAUAUAUUUUUUGAUGGAGUCUCACUCUGUCGCCCAGACUGGAGUGCAAGUGGGGUGAUUUUGGCUCACUGCAACCUCCACCUCCUGGGUUCAUGUGAUUUUCCUGCCUCAGCCUCCCGAGUAGCUGAGAUUACAGGUGCCCGCCACCACACUCAGCUAAUUUUUGCAUUUUUAGUAGAGAUGAGGUUUCACCAUGUUGGCCAGGCUGGUCUCAAACUCCUGACUGCAGGUGAUCCACCUGCCUUGGCCUCCCAAAGUGCGGGGAUUAUAGGAGUGAGCCACCAUGCCUGACCGGAAAAUACGAUCUUGAGGUAGGGAAGUAUUUCUUAGACAAGAUCUAGACAAAGCAAAAGUGAAAGACUGAUAAAAUGUAACUAUGUGAAAACCUAAAAUAUUUGUGCACCAAAAUUCACCAUAAGCAAAGUAGAAAGACAAGCCACGCUGAGGAAAGAUUCUUGCAGUGCACAGAAAUGAGAAAGGUUUAACAUUCAGAAUACAUGAAGAAUUCCUAUAAGGUAAUGAGAAAUACCAAACCAAACCAAAACCUCUCAAUAGAAUAACACUCAAAAGAUAUAAACAGAUUAUUCAAAGAGUUGAAAUCUGAUGAAAUAAACAUGCUUAAUCUCAUUAACAACCAGAAAUACAAACUAAAACCUCAAUGAGGUAGGUACCAUUUCACCCACCAGACUGCAAAAACUACCAAGUUUUGUUAAAGAUACAAAGCAACAAGAAUUCUUUUAUAUAUUGAUAGUGGGUAUUCAAACUGGUAUAGCCCCUUUGUAAAACAAUUUAGCAAUAUUUAGUAAUGAAUAUGUAAACUGUGAUAUGUAUAUAUUAUAUAUGUAUGUGAUAUAUAAAUGUUUGAUAUAUGUAUGUGUAUAUAUAACCACAUAGAUGAAUCUCAUGAUUACAAAGUCAAGGGGAAAAAGAAAACGACAGAUGAAUGCAUAUAAUAUGUAUUAUAAUUUAAUAUGAAGUUUUAAAACAUGCAAAACAAAACCAUAGUAAAAUAAGAAGAGCAUGGGAAUGAUAUCAAAUUUAAAAAAGUAGUUAUCUGGGGAUGGGGUAGGUAUAGAGGGGACUUCAACUGGAUGGGUCAUGUUUUAUUUCUUAUACUGAAUGGUGAGUUCAAAGGUCUUUGUUAUGUUAUCCAUACUUUUCUGCAUAACAAAUGUUUCAUAAUAUAUUUUUUAAAAAUCGGAUGAAUUGUGCUACAUAAAUAGCUUGAGUAAAAAAAAGUGUGAGGGUUUGGGGACUUACUACUGAAGCCUGUUUAUUCAUUCUGAUCUGCCAACCAUUUUUAGGUCUUCAAGAAAAUUAAAAUGCAAGCAGCCAAAUGCCUUUGUCUUUAUAAGCUGUGGAAACUAUAAAAACUGAAUGUUUCAGUCUGA